GCAAAGCCGACCGAGACGGAGCCGCUGUCAACUCUCCAACUCAGCUCAGCUGAUCGGUUGCCGCCGCCGCCGCCGCCAGAUUCUGGAGGCGAAGAACGCAAAGCUGAGAACAUGGACGUUAAUAUCGCCCCACUCCGCGCCUGGGACGAUUUCUUCCCGGGUUCCGAUCGCUUUGCCCGGCCGGACUUCAGGGACAUUUCCAAAUGGAACAACCGCGUAGUGAGCAACCUGCUCUAUUACCAGACCAACUACCUGGUGGUGGCUGCCAUGAUGAUUUCCAUUGUGGGGUUUCUGAGUCCCUUCAACAUGAUCCUGGGAGGAAUCGUGGUGGUGCUGGUGUUCACAGGGUUUGUGUGGGCAGCCCACAAUAAAGACGUCCUUCGCCGGAUGAAGAAGCGCUACCCCACGACGUUCGUUAUGGUGGUCAUGUUGGCGAGCUAUUUCCUUAUCUCCAUGUUUGGAGGAGUCAUGGUCUUUGUGUUUGGCAUUACUUUUCCUUUGCUGUUGAUGUUUAUCCAUGCAUCGUUGAGACUUCGGAACCUCAAGAACAAACUGGAGAAUAAAAUGGAAGGAAUAGGUUUGAAGAGGACACCGAUGGGCAUUGUCCUGGAUGCCCUAGAACAGCAGGAAGAAGGCAUCAACAGACUCACUGACUAUAUCAGCAAAGUGAAGGAAUAAACAUAACUUACCUGAGCUAGGGUUGCAGCAGAAAUUGAGUUGCAGCUUGCCCUUGUCCAGACCUAUGUUCUGCUUGCGUUUUUGAAACAGGAGGUGCACGUACCACCCAAUUAUCUAUGGCAGCAUGCAUGUAUAGGCCGAACUAUUAUCAGCUCUGAUGUUUCAGAGAGAAGACCUCAGAAACCGAAAGAAAACCACCACCCUCCUAUUGUGUCUGAAGUUUCACGUGUGUUUAUGAAAUCUAAUGGGAAAUGGAUCACACGAUUUCUUUAAGGGAAUUAAAAAAAAUAAAAGAAUUACGGCUUUUACAGCAACAAUACGAUUAUCUUAUAGGAAAAAAAAAAUCAUUGUAAAGUAUCAAGACAAUACGAGUAAAUGAAAAGGCUGUUAAAGUAGAUGACAUCAUGUGUUAGCCUGUUCCUAAUCCCCUAGAAUUGUAAUGUGUGGGAUAUAAAUUAGUUUUUAUUAUUCUCUUAAAAAUCAAAGAUGAUCUCUAUCACUUUGCCACCUGUUUGAUGUGCAGUGGAAACUGGUUAAGCCAGUUGUUCAUACUUCCUUUACAAAUAUAAAGAUAGCUGUUUAGGAUAUUUUGUUACAUUUUUGUAAAUUUUUGAAAUGCUAGUAAUGUGUUUUCACCAGCAAGUAUUUGUUGCAAACUUAAUGUCAUUUUCCUUAAGAUGGUUACAGCUAUGUAACCUGUAUUAUUCUGGACGGACUUAUUAAAAUACAAACAGACAAAAAAUAAAACAAAACUUGAGUUCUAUUUACCUUGCACAUUUUUUGUUGUUACAGUGAAAAAAAUGGUCCAAGAAAAUGUUUGCCAUUUUUGCAUUGUUUCGUUUUUAACUGGAACAUUUAGAAAGAAGGAAAUGAAUGUGCAUUUUAUUAAUUCCUUAGGGGCACAAGGAGGACAAUAAUAGCUGAUCUUUUGAAAUUUGAAAAACGUCUUUAGAUGACCAAGCAAAAAGACUUUAAAAAAUGGUAAUGAAAAUGGAAUGCAGCUACUGCAGCUAAUAAAAAAUUUUAGAUAGCAAUUGUUACAACCAUAUGCCUUUAUAGCUAGACAUUAGAAUUAUGAUAGCAUGAGUUUAUACAUUCUAUUAUUUUUCCUCCCUUUCUCAUGUUUUUAUAAAUAGGUAAUAAAAAAUGUUUUGCCUGCCAAUUGAAUGAUUUCGUAGCUGAAGUAGAAACAUUUAGGUUUCUGUAGCAUUAAAUUGUGAAGACAACUGGAGUGGUACUUACUGAAGAAACUCUCUGUAUGUCCUAGAAUAAGAAGCAAUGAUGUGCUGCUUCUGAUUUUUCUUGCAUUUUAAAUUCUCAGCCAACCUACAGCCAUGAUCUUUAGCACAGUGAUAUCACCAUGACUUCACAGACAUGGUCUAGAAUCUGUACCCUUACCCACAUAUGAAGAAUAAAAUUGAUUAAAGGUUUUUUUGGUGAGACUUUAUUUAAUGCA